CCUUUAGUCACUUCCAGCUCCAGGCACAGCAGUUGGUGACUCCUUGGUGGGAGCCGUGUCCCACCCGGUCCUGAUACUGCCGUCUUCUCUUUCACAGUCCUCCAGGCUUGGGCCAGCCUUGGGGGCAGCAGAGCUUCUGGGCUGACAUGGGCUCAUUGCUCCUUCUCCAAGCCCUCUGAGGACAUCAAAAGCGUGGACGCAUCACUUUCCACCAUCUUGCUGCCCACUGUCCCUCCAUCCUGAGGCCUCCUAAGCACAUGUGUGGGGUGGCAGGCACACUGCUGAUAGCUGUGGAUGCGGCCGUGACAUCCUUCACCCCUGCCCCCAUGGCAUGCAUGAUCCAUUAGGGAGGACCGUCUGCACAAAGGUCUCUUGCCCUGUGCAGCUUCCUGCAGACUGGACUUGCAAAGUCCAGCCUGUAUGGCUGGAGUUCCCAUGCCUGCCAAUCUCCUGUCGACUGCGAGUCAGCUCCGAUACUUCACCAGAUUCAGCCACCUGGGGGAGCUGGAAGUGAAUCUCAUCUUAGCUGAGCCUUCUGAUGAGACUGCAGCCCCAGCUGACACCUGGAUUGCAGACUCAUGAAAGACCUGAAACUCUACCAACAGCCACCUGGGGGAGCUGGAAGUGAAUCUCCUCGUAGCUGAGCCUUCUGAUGAGACUGCAGCCCCGGCUGACACCUGGAUUGCAGACUCAUGAAAGACCUGAAACUCUACCAACAGCCACCUGGGGGAGCUGGAAGUGAAUCUCCUCGUAGCUGAGCCUUCUGAUGAGACUGCAGCCCCGGCUGACACCUGGAUUGCAGACUCAUGAAAGACCCUGAGCAGAGGACCCAGUUUGGCAGAGCCCGAAUUCCUGACCCACAGGAACUGGGAGAUAAAACUCUGUGGUUUUAAUCUUCUCAUUUUAGAGUGCUCAGUGUCCUGUGGUGUGAACACGCUUCAUUCAACCUGGGCCCUUGGGAGAGAUGCUGAGUGGUUCCCGGGCUGUCCCCACUCCACACCGUGGCAGUGAAGAGCUGCUGAAGUACAUGCUUCAUAGUCCUUGCGUCUCUCUGACCAUGAAUGGCACCUACAACACCUGUGGCUCCAGCGACCUCACCUGGCCCCCAGCGAUCAAGCUGGGCUUCUACGCCUACUUGGGCGUCCUGCUGGUGCUAGGCCUGCUGCUCAACAGCCUGGCGCUCUGGGUGUUCUGCUGCCGCAUGCAGCAGUGGACGGAGACCCGCAUCUACAUGACCAACCUGGCGGUGGCCGACCUCUGCCUGCUGUGCACCUUGCCCUUCGUGCUGCACUCCCUGCGAGACACCUCAGACACGCCGCUGUGCCAGCUCUCCCAGGGCAUCUACCUGACCAACAGGUACAUGAGCAUCAGCCUGGUCACGGCCAUCGCCGUGGACCGCUAUGUGGCCGUGCGGCACCCGCUGCGUGCCCGCGGGCUGCGGUCCCCCAGGCAGGCUGCGGCCGUGUGCGCGGUCCUCUGGGUGCUGGUCAUCGGCUCCCUGGUGGCUCGCUGGCUCCUGGGGAUUCAGGAGGGCGGCUUCUGCUUCAGGAGCACCCGGCACAAUUUCAACUCCAUGGCGUUCCCGCUGCUGGGAUUCUACCUGCCCCUGGCCGUGGUGGUCUUCUGCUCCCUGAAGGUGGUGACUGCCCUGGCCCAGAGGCCACCCACCGACGUGGGGCAGGCAGAGGCCACCCGCAAGGCUGCCCGCAUGGUCUGGGCCAACCUCCUGGUGUUCGUGGUCUGCUUCCUGCCCCUGCACGUGGGGCUGACAGUGCGCCUCGCAGUGGGCUGGAACGCCUGUGCCCUCCUGGAGACGAUCCGUCGCGCCCUGUACAUAACCAGCAAGCUCUCAGAUGCCAACUGCUGCCUGGACGCCAUCUGCUACUACUACAUGGCCAAGGAGUUCCAGGAGGCGUCUGCACUGGCCGUGGCUCCCAGUGCUAAGGCCCACAAAAGCCAGGACUCUCUGUGCGUGACCCUCGCCUAAGAGGCGUGCUGUGGGCGCUGUGGGCCAGGUCUCGGGGGCUCCGGGAGGUGCUGCCUGCCAGGGGAAGCUGGAACCAGUAGCAAGGAGCCCGAGAUCAGCCCUGAACUCACUGUGUAUUCUCUUGGAGCCUUGGGUGGGCAGGGACGGCCCAGGUACCUGCUCUCUUGGGAAGAGAGAGGGACAGGGACAAGGGCAAGAGGACUGAGGCCAGAGCAAGGCCAAUGUCAGAGACCCCCGGGAUGGGGCCUCACACUUGCCACCCCCAGAACCAGCUCACCUGGCCAGAGUGGGUUCCUGCUGGCCAGGGUGCAGCCUUGAUGACACCUGCCGCUGCCCCUCGGGGCUGGAAUAAAACUCCCCACCCAGAGUCAGUCCUAGUGGGGCCCUCUGUGUUUCGCACUCGUGUGGUGGGAGGCAGGGAGGGAGCGCGUGGCUCAGAGGGCUGGCGGACAUCUUCCAGGGACCCUUCGGGGCUCUUCACUUUGAGGUCCCCCUUGGACCCUUUCACCCCUUCCCACCCCCACCCACCUGGAGCGUGAGCAGGGGCUGUUGGAAGCUCCUGGCAGGACCACAGUAGAGGCCCCCAGCCCAGGUUUCCUUGCUCAAGACAGGGCUGGGAGCAGCUGAUCUCCAUGUAGGGGCUGCACAGCGGUGCAAGGGGGGGUGACCAAGGUCAAGCAGGUGAGGGUGGGUUGGGGUGGGUGGCAGUGAAGGGGGUGGCCAGGGUCUGUCAAGGAACCCAGCCCUCUUCUCCUUCCUUCAGGGAAAGGCUGGAAACCAUGUCUGGCAGGGGCAGGGGUUGGGUGCCCACUCAGGUAAAGGCACGAUGUCCUGCUGGUUUCUGCCUCUCCUGUACUCCUGCAUGGAGGGCAUCUCGAAACCCAAGCUGGAAGGACAGGGCACUCCAGAGACCUCCUGUGAGUGUGGGCCAGCACGGCCUGGGCUCAAACCCCAUCCUGUCAUCCCAUAUUGCAUGUCCACAGGCACCGCCCCACCCUGUUCCAUGUUCCACAGGACUGGAGAGAGAUGGCAGUCAUGUUCUGGCAGGGACAUGGCACAAGCAUGCGGCUGAUGGCAUCUCACAGGACCCAGGCUCCGGAGGGCCCAUGCCCAGGAGAGCCCCAUAAGGGCUCUGUGCCUAAAAGGGUGCAUGCCCAGGUGGGCCCAUGCCCAGGAAGGUCCAUGCCCAGGAUGGUCCAUGAGCAGGAGGGCCUCAUUCCCAGGAGGGUCCCGUGCCCAGGAGGGCUCUAUGCCCAAAAGGGUCCCAUGUCCGGGAGGGUCCAUACGCAAGGGUGUCCAUGCCUGGUUGGGGGGGGUCUAUGUCCAGGAGGGUCCCAUGCCUGGAAGGGUCCAUGCUCAGGAGGGUUCAUGCCCAGGAGAGUUUAUGCCCUGGAGGGCCCCAUGCCCGGGAGAGUCACGUGCACAGAGGGCCCUGUGCUCAGGAGGAUACAUGUCCAGGAGUGUCCCUGUCCAGGAGGCUCCAUGCCCAGGAGGCUCCAUGUCAAGAAAGAUUCAUGCCUAGGAGGGUUCAUGCCCAGGAGUGUCCCUGCCUAGGAAGAUCCAUUACCAGAAGGGCCCAUGUCAAGGAGCGUUCAUGCCCAGGAAGGUCCAGCCCAGGAGGGUCCAUGUCAAGGAGGUUCCAUGCCCAGGAGGGUCCAUGCUGAGGUGGGUCCAUGCCCAGGAGGGUUCAUGUCCAGAAAGGUCCAUGCCUAGGAGGGCCCAUACACAACAGAGCCCUGUGCCCAGGAAGGACCAUGUCAAGGAGAACCCCAUGCCCAUGAGGGUCCAUGCCCAGUAAGGGCCAUGCCCAUGAGAUCCUCAUGCCCAGGAAGGCCCAUGCCCAGGAGGGUCCAUGCCCAGGCCAGUUCAUGCACAGGAGGGCCCCAUGCCUAAAAGUGUCCAUGCCCAGGAAGGUCCAUGUCCAGAAGAGUCCAUACCCAGGAGGGCUGAUAUGGUUAGGCUUUGUGUCUCCACCCAAAUCUCAUCUUGAAUUGUAAUCCCUAUAAUAACCAUAGUCCCCAUGUGUCAAGGGAGAGACCAGGUGGAGGCAAUUGGAUCAUGGGGGCUGUUUCCCACAUGCUGUUCUCAUGAUAGUGAGUGAGUUCUCAUGAGAUCUGAUGGUUUUAUAAGGGGCUCUUCCCUUCACUUCUCCUUCCUACUGUCUUAUGAAGAAGGUUCCUUGCUUCCCCUUCACCUUCUGCCAUGAUUGUAAGUUUCCUGAGGCCUCCCUAGCCAUGCUGAAGUGUGAGUCAAUUAAACCUCUUUCCUUUAAAAUUA